CUAUUUUCUCACCUGGUUCCCGCGGCGAGCCAGCGGCAGCGGCGGCGGCGAUGAGACAGAAGCACUACCUUGAGGCUGCAGCGCGGGGACUGCACGACAGCUGCCCGGGCCAAGCCCGCUACCUCCUGUAAGAGGACUGGAGGGGAAGCGGGAGGCGAGCGGGUAGGUGUUCCUUUGCUCCUCACAAGUCUCUUUCUCUUUUACAGCUGGGCCUACACUUCGUCGCACGAUGAUAAGAGCACUUUUGAAGAAACGUGUCCAUACUGUUUCCAGCUGUUGGUUCUGGAUAACUCUCGAGUGCGUCUCAAACCCAAAGCCAGGUUGACACCCAAAAUACAGAAACUUCUUAAUCGAGAAGCGAGAAACUAUACACUCAGUUUUAAAGAAGCAAAAAUGGUGAAAAAGUUCAAAGACUCCAAAAGUGUAUUGUUGAUCACUUGUAAAACAUGCAACAGAACAGUGAAACAUCAUGGUAAAAGUAGAAGCUUUGUGUCAACAUUGAAGAGCAAUCCUGCCACUCCUACAAGUAAACUCAGCCUGAAGACACCAGAGAGAAGGACUGCAAACCCAAAUCAUGACAUGUCUGGCUCGAAAGGCAAGAGCCCAGCAUCGGUUUUCAGAACACCUACAUCUGGACAGUCAGUAUCUACUUGCUCCUCAAAGAACACCAGCAAAACAAAGAAACACUUCUCUCAACUAAAAAUGUUACUUAGUCAGAAUGAAUCCCAAAAGAUUCCAAAGGUGGACUUCAGAAAUUUCUUAUCUUCUCUGAAGGGUGGACUUUUAAAAUAAGAAAUGCCUGAUGUCAAUUCUGAAACUAAAGUUGGUAAAACAACUUUUUAAACUCUUAUUCAUUUUUUGAAUACAUGGAAACUAGAUCUGAAUGCAAACUUUUCUUGGCAUCCUUCAGUGUUUAUGGGGAAAAUACCUCAUUAGUGUGAAUACCUGAAACCUGCCUACCUCAUAGGACAGCUGUGAGGAUCAAAAAAUAUAUGAAAGUUCCUUGUAGAUACAUAUCUAUAGAUAUAUAUGUGUAUGUAUAUAAAGAUAGAUAUAUACAUUGA